AGUCAGCAAGGUUGCGCGUGCCCUGUGAGACCGCCAAGAUGGUGGUGGGCGCGUUCCCUAUGGCGAAGCUGCUAUACUUGGGCAUCCGGCAGGUCAGCAAGCCGCUUGCCAACCGUAUUAAGGAGGCCGCCCGCCGAAGCGAGUUCUUCAAGACCUAUAUCUGCCUCCCGCCGGCUCAACGAGUGAGUCAGGAUGCAGCAUCAAUUCUGCAUUGGUUUUAAAGACUCAAGUGCUGAGAACCUUCCUUCAUAAAGAAGCAGCUAGGCAAGGAAGGAGUUUUUGUUCCAGCAGCACCACUCACCUCUUGAGCUCCCACCAAGUGUAUCACUGGGUGGAGAUGCGGACCAAGAUGCGCAUCAUGGGCUUCCGGGGCACGGUCAUCAAGCCGCUGAACGAGGAGGCGGCAGCUGAGCUGGGCGCAGAGCUGCUGGGCGAAGCCACCAUCUUCAUCGUGGGCGGCGGCUGCCUAGUGCUGGAGUACUGGCGCCACCAGGCGCAGCAGCGCCACAAGGAGGAGGAGCAGCGUGCUGCCUGGAACGCGCUGCGGGACGAGGUGGGCCACCUGGCGCUGGCGCUGGAAGCGCUGCAGGCGCAGGUGCAGGCGGCGCCGCCACAGGGCGCCCUGGAGGAACUGCGCACAGAGCUGCAAGAGGUGCGCGCCCAGCUCUGCAAUCCCGGCCGGUCCGCUUCCCACGCAGUGCCUGCGUCCAAGAAAUAGGAGCUUGCUGGAUGGAACCUGAAUUUGGACAUGGCCUAUGUACCUAACGUGGCCUUCUUCCCGCACCACCCUUGCCUGCGCUGGCCCAGUGGAAACCACCAGGAUCUUGAUGCAACUUGGCAUUUGGUUACCCCUGCUGAUAAGAGCAGCCGUUACCUGCCACUGGGACCAGCAGGUGAAGCGUUGCAACAUAGCCCCCUCCAUCAUCCUUCACCUCCUAUCCCCCACUCCAAACCAGGACGACCUGCAAGGUCCCAGCCAGCAGGACACCGUGGGCACUCUGGCAAAUGAAAAAAUGGAACCUGGUCUUGAGCUGAAUCAAUGUGUUAUUGUUACCCCCACCCCCGGUUUACCUGAUCAGUGUUAACCUUUACUGGGACACUCAUCUGUUACACUGGAACACCUUCUUCUUUUUGUCAAUCGGCACAGACCACUGUAAGGAAAUGCAGUGUGUUGCAGUGGCCUUUUCUCCCCCUCACCUUCUAAGGUCAGCUCUAGCUGAGCAUCAGUGCUCUCUUAAGGAGGAAAAAAACGGUGCGGCUGGGAGCGGUGGCUCACGCCUGUAAUCCUAGCACCUUGGGAGGCCGAGGCGGGCGGAUCACUUGAGGUCAGGAGUUCCAGACCAGCCUGGCCAACAUGGUGAAACUCCGUCUCUACUAAAAAUACAAAAAUUAGCCGGGUGUGGUGGGGUGCGCUUGUAAUCCCAGCUACUCGGGAGGCUGAGGCAGGAGAAUUGCUUGAACCCAUGAGGUGGAGGUUGCGGUGAGCCAAGAUGGCACCAUUGCACCCUAGCCUGGGCAACAGAGCAAGACACCGUCUUAAAACCAAAAGUUAACCGGGCGUGGUGGUGGGUGCCUGUAAUCCUAGCUACUUGGGAGGCUGAGGCAGGAGAAUUGCUUGAACUUGGGAGGUGGAGGCCAAGAUUGUACCACUGUAUUCCAGCCCGGGUGACAGAGCAAGACUGUGUCUCAAAAAAAAAAAAAAAAUCCUGGCUGGGCACGGUGGCUCACACCUGCAAUCCCAGCACUUUGGAAGGUCGAGGUGGGCGGGUCAUUUGAAGUCGGGAGGUCGGGAGAUCGGGAGCUCGAGACCAGCCUGACCAAUAUGAUGAAACCCCGUCUCUACUAAAAAUACAUAAAUUAGCUGGGCAUGGUGGCAUGCACCUGUAAUCCCAGCUACUUGGGAGGCUGAGACAGGAGAAUUGCUUGAACCCGGGAGGCAGAGGUUGCAGUGAGCCGAGAUUGCGCAAUUGCAUGCCAGCCUGGGUAACGAGCAAAACUCCAUCUUAAAAAAACCCACAAAAGGUCCUGGCCUGCAGUCAAUCCCUGGAAUCAUUGUACCUUCCCUUGAGACCCGAAGUGGACUAUUCCAACAGAACCCCCUCAUCCUUGAGUCUAUGGCACAACCCACUGGAAUGGCACUACAGGAUCUUUUCUGUGAAUGUCCUCCAACCCCCCUUUCCGUGGUGGGAAAUUUGAUCCUAACUAGGGCUAAUCCAGCCUGUCCUUCAGCCUCAGCCCCCUAUUUUCCUGUCCUCAGAGUCCCUGGAGCUUGUACUGUGUGGCAUGUCCUUUCUUGCCUUCCCCACCUUGCUCAGUAGCAUUUCUCAGGGACCCAGUCGAAUCCAAGCCCAUGGAUUCAAUUGUCACAUCCUUCAUCUUCCAUCCGUGUCUCCUAAUCUGUGUGCUCUUGCUUUCUUUCCUCGGAGCUCUGGACUGACCCGACAGCCUGUCUUCAUGUAGCAGUACCCUCCUGCCUCCAUAGCCCCCGGUCCCACCCCCAUCCUACCAAUUAGGCCAGCAGUUGGCCUUAACUGCUUGAUUAAUUUCCUUGGACUGCCAUAACAGAUCACCAUUGGGUGGUGAACUUGAUGGCUUAAGUCCAACAGGAAUUUAAUUCACACAGUUCUGGAGUCCAGAAGUCUGAAACCAAGGUGCUGACAGGGACACGCUCCCUCUUCCAGCUCCUGGUGAUUCCAGGCCUUCCUUGGCUCUGCCUGCAGCUUCACAUGGCCUUUUCCCUCUUCUAUUUUGUCUCUUACAAGAACACCUGUCAUUGCAUUUAGGGCCCAUCUUAAGUUCAGGAUGAUCCCACCUCAAGACCCUUAAUUACAUCUGAAAAAACACUUUUUCCAAAUAAACUGUCAUAAGCACAGGUCCUGGGGGUUAGUAUGUGGACUUGUCUGUUGGGGGCACACCAUUCAAGCCAUUCAGCCCACUAUUCCUCCUCACCCCAAGAGUACGCUGGCGUCCAGGUGCAGUGGCUCACACCUGUAAUCCCAGCACUUUGGGAGACCAGGGCAGGAGGGAUCUCUUUGAGCCCAGGAGCUGAAGACCAGCCUGGGCAACAUAGUGAGACCCCAUCUCUACAAAAGUAAAAUAAAAAAUUAGCCAGGUGCGGUGAUGCAUGCCUGUAGUCCCAGCUACUUGGGAGGCUGAGGCAGGAGGAUCACCUGAGCCCUGGAGGUCGAGGCUGCAGCGAGCCGUGAUCGCGCCACUACACUCCAGCCUGGAUGACAGAGUGAGACCCUUUCUCAGAAAAAAAGUACCCUGGGACUCCUGCCAACCCCGCGGGCCAUUUGGCCUUCCUGCUAGCUGAGAGGAACAGUCUAGGAACCACCCUUUUCUACUGGGUUUCUCUUCCAGGAUCUGCCACUGAAGCGGGAGGGGGUGGGUCCCAGUAGCCUGCAGUCUGUCCUUCCGACUGUAGCUCUCUCAUUAGAGGAGCUGCAAGGUGAUGAAGGCAUCCUGAGGCUGUACCUGAACCACCAUGUGGAUCUCCACAAUGGGUACAGAGCUUAUUAAAAUCAGGAGGGAAACUGGGAGGGUUCUGAUGGGGAGAGGCCCAAGAGUCACCCUAUGAGCUGGGGAAACUAAGGCCAGGGGUAAGCAAAGGGACUUGCCAGAGAUGCCACAGCCAGUGAGGGGCUGACUGCCCAGGGUGGUGAAGUAGUAGGGGCAGAGUGAGAGGCUUGGAUUACCCCAGCUGCAGAGUGAGGAGGGAGAGGCGAUGGCUGAGCAGAGGCUGGGAGGGUGACGAUCUCUACACAGAGGCCCAGACCAUCCCAGAGGUGGCGUUGAUAGUGGGAGACCCUCUCUAUCCCCUCUCAGAGCAGCCCCAGAUCACACCAGAGAUCAUAGCAUUGUGUAAACUGGGUGACCAUUCCACCUGGGCCCGCUUUUGGGAAGCUGCAGGUGAAAGUGGGAGGGCCGGGCUUUCCCCGACUUCCAUCCUCACCUCCCUUCUCUAAAGAGGUAAAACUGGCCUGGACCAAGAUCUGCCCAGAUAGAAAGCCAAGAAACAGGUUCUGAAACUUUUCUUUUCUUCUUUUCUCUUCUUUUUUCUUUUCUUUUCUUUCGGAGACAGUCUAGCUCCGUCACCCUGACGGAGUGCAGUGGUGCAAUCUCGGCUCACUGCAACUUCUACCUCCCAGGCUCAACCAAUGAUCCUGCCUCAGCUUCCGAAGUAGCUGGGAUUACAUGUGCCCACCACCCACGCCUGGCUAAUUUUUGUAUUUUAGUGGAGACGGGGUUUCUCCAAGUUGCCCAGGCUGAUCUUGAACUCCUGACCUCAGGUAAUCCGCCCGCCUCGGCCUCCCAAAGUGCUGGGAUUACAGGCGUGAGCCACCGCGCCUGGCCUGAAACAGCAUUUCAGUUCCUUCUGGAAGAGGGGGAGAAGCUGGAGCAGAGGGAACUGACCGAGUGGGUCCUGAGUGGGCUGUGUUUAAAACUGGGAGUGACCCAGGCCAGCUCACGCCUGUCAUCCCAGCACUUUGAGAGGCCAAGGUGGACUGAUCACAUGAUGUUAGGAGAUCGAGACCAGCCUGGCCAACAUGGCAAAACCCCGUCUCUACUAAAAAUACAAAAAUUAGCCGGGCAUGUUGGCACAUUCCUGAAUCCCAGCUACUCGGGAGGCUGAGGCACGAGAAUUGCUUGAACCCAGGAGGUGGAGGUUGCAGUGAGCUGAGAUCGCGCCACUGCACUCCAGCCUGGGUGACAGAGUGAGACUCAACUCAAAAAAAAAAAACAGAGGUGGGAGUGUGAACACAGGCAGGAGCUCCAAUUCCUGACCCCAGCGCUGUCCUGACCCAGAUGGAGUGCUGCUCUCACAUCUCAGAGACUUCGCACUCAGCCCUGCCCUGCCCUGCCCUGACAGGCAGCCAGUCAUCGUGGGCAGCAGGGCCAUCUACUUCCCCCACUGCGGCGUCAGGGGUGGCCAGAGUGUGUGGAAGUGGAAAGAACGUCCUCUCAAAAUGCAAGAGGCCAGAGGAUGGUUCACUGCUCGUGUGUUCUGCUAGCUAGAAUUCUGUGUACCUUGUAAUUUGGGGAGAGGGGUUAGAAUAAAUUUGUAAAUGAAGCUGAUUAUCUUCAAGUUGAUGCAUUCUUUUUUCAUAUUUAAAAAGUCCUUGGGACUGGGCGCAGUGGCUCACACCUGUAAUCCUAGCACUUUGGGAGGCCAGGGUGGGUGGAUCACCUGAGGUCAGGAGUUCAAGACCAACCUGAUCAACAUGGUGAAACCUCGUCUCUACUAAAAAUACAAAAAUUAGCUGGGCAUGGUGGUUGUGCACCUGUAAUCCCACCUACUCGGGAGGCUGAGGCAGGAGAAUCUCUUGGACCCGGGAGGCGGAGGUUGCAGUGAGCCGAGAUCAUGCCAUUAUACUCCAGCCUGGGUGACAGAGCGAGACUUCAUCUCUAAAUAAAUAAAUAAAUAAAUAAAUAAAUAAGGUCCAUGUCAACCUUAGGAAAAAUAUCCUUUAUUUAUUCUUUCACUCAAAAAACUCACUGAGGUGGUCCCGCACCGGGACAUGGACCCAGUGUCCUUGGUAGGGCGUCUCCCGCAAAAAAAAAAAAAAUAAAAAAAAUAAAACACAAAACUCACUGAGUUACCCACUCUCUGCCCCACCCUAUGCUGGGGUCACAGUGGUGACAGAGACAGCCCCAGCCCUGCCGUCACCGGGUCUUACAGAUGCUCACACGUACAUUUCUUUUCCAGUGUUCCCUGCCCCACCCCAUAGUUGUUUAGGAAGCAGGGGCUGGGCUGAAUCCGGAAUCCUCCCUCUGGAGUGACUCAGGACUAUAAACCCAUUCAUCCCAGCUCACAAAACCCUGGGAGGUGCCCUGAGGGCUGUGCCCCUCCCAUCUCCUGGCAGGCCCUGCUGUCCCUCUUGUUGGUUUCUCUGUAGGGCAGGCCAUUGCCUGGAGGGAGGCAAAAUGGCUGAGAGCCACCCCAGGAGAAAAUGGGCUUUACAUAAGCCCCAACCUGAUCUAUUGGCUCACGGAGCUACUCCUGGGCUGGUCGCUGUGUUGCUGAGUGGCAGGCUUGGGUCCCCCAGUGGCAAUGGCUUGUAGCUGGAGUCGGUGUGGACAGAGAGAGGAGAAGCAUGGCAACUCUGAGUGUACUGAGGAUCAACUGCACCAGGCUCCAUUCUAGUAGCUGGGAGCCAGUUGGGAGCAAGCAGAGGCCCUCACUGGAGCUGACAUUCUAGUGCCAGAGACCGGCAAUAAAGAAGGAAAGAGUGGCCAGGCGUGGUGGCUCACACCUGUAAUCUCAGCACUUUGGGAGGCCGAGGCGGGCCAAUCCCCUGAGGUCGGGAGUUCGAGACCAGCCUGACCGACAUGGAGAAACCCCAUCUCUACUAAAAAUACAAAAUUAGCAGGGCAUGGUGGUGCAUGCCUGUAAUCCCAGCCACUCAGGAGGCUGUGGCAGGAGAAUCGCUUGAACCCGGGAGGCGGAGGUUGCGGUGAGCCAAUAUUGCACCAUUGCACUCCAGCCUGGGCAACAAGAACGAGACUCCAUCUCAAAAAAAAAAGGAAAAAGCUAAUCCAGCAUAGGGUGAUGAGGACUGAGAGGAAUGGAGGCAGGGUAGGAGUUCCGGACUUACGGGCACCGCUGAUCUAGACAGGUGGGCAGGGAGGAGGCAGCGCUUCAGAUGGAGGGAGAUAGGAAGAGGGCUGUGAGUAUCUGUGAAAGUCCUAGGACAGAUGUGGCCUUGGCCUGUUCCUGGAACAGCAAGAGUUUCUGGCUGUCAGAAUAGAGCAGAGGCUCGCUGACCAAGGCCUUUGGGCCAAAUCAAGGGGACCCUUGCUUCCUGUCUUUGUAAAUAAAGACUUAUUGGAACCCAGGCGCUCAUUCGUUUGCAUAUUUUCCACAGUUGCUUUUGCAGUACAGUGACAGAGCUGAGUAUUUGCACAGAGAUCCUAGGGCUCUCGUACUCUCUGGCCCUUUACAGAAAAAGUUUACCAUCCCCUGGAAUAGAGUAAGCGAGGGGAGAAGUUAGGUGAGGGGGCCAGGCAAGCAAAGGCUGCCCCUUGCCUUGAUUGGCACAACUGUGGAGGUCAUCCCAGCUCUGGAGCCCCAACAGGAUCACUCAGGCCUCUGCUUCCACCACAUCUGGCUUCAGCUUCCCCCUCUGUGGAGUCCUCCCUCCCUCCCUCCUUCCCCAUAGGAAAUGACCCCAGUGCUCAGCAGUAACCCCCACUGCGCGCAGAUCUCAGAACCUCCACCUCAAUCUACAGCCACGUGCCACAAUAAGAAGCAGAGUUUUAGGCCAGGCGCGGUGGCUCACGCCUGUAAUCUCAGUACUUUGGAAGACCAAGGUGGGAGGAUCACUUGAAGUCAGGAGUUCGAGACCAGCCUGCCCAACAUGGUGAAGCCCCGUCUCUAAUAAAAAGAAUACAAAAAUUAGCCGGGUGUGGUGGUGCACAUCUGUAAUCCCAGCUACAUGAGAGGCUGACAUAGGAGAAUUGCUUGAGCCCAGGAGGUGGACGUUGCAGUGAGCCAAGAUUGCACUACUGCAUUCCAGCCUAGGUGCCAGAGUGAGACUUGGUCUCAAAACAAAACAAAACAAAAAAUUAGCCAGGCAUGGUGGCACACACCUGUAGUCCCAGCUACUUGGGGGGCUGAGGCAGGAGGAUCGCUUGAACCCGGGUGUUUAAGGCUGCAGUGAACUGAGAUCAGGCCACAGCACCUCAACCUGGGAGACAAAGUGAGACCCUGUCUCAAAAAAAAAAAAAAGCAGAGUUUAUGUAAUCCAUCGUGUGCAUAUUUAUACAAUAAUUUACAAUUCUAUGUAUUUUAAAAGUGUAUAAUUCAUAUAUUAUGUGACACAAUAUAUAAUGGAAUAUAAAAUAUAUAUUUUAUGUCAUGUGUAACAUAACAUCAUCUAUUAUAUGUAGUGUAUGUGCUUAUGUACAUAUCAUUGGAAUGAAAGUUUCAUUAAAUAAUUACCCUUAA